AGGCGCCUGAGAGGCUCUCUACCGGUGAGGGUUUGCGGGGAAGAUGGAGUAUCCCGCGCCGGCCACGGUGCAGGCCGCGGACGGCGGAGCGGCCGGGCCUUACAGCAGCUCGGAGUUGCUGGAGGGCCAGGAGCCGGACGGGGUGCGCUUUGACCGCGAGAGGGCGCGCCGCCUGUGGGAAGCCGUGUCCGGUGCCCAGCCGGUGGGUAGAGAGGAAGCGCAGUUUUUCCCACAUUCGAGGACUGUCAUCCCUAUACUCGUCCUGUCGGAGACCUACAGUCUUUGCCAUCCCGAGCCAGCUGCUUGAUGCUAACCCAGAUGUACAAGAACUCUAUCUGGGCUUCUCUGCUAACCUUGUCAGUGGAGCACAUGAUCCAGAAGAACCAAUGUCUCUUCACCAACACCCAGUGUAAGGUUUGCUGCGCCUUGCUUAUUUCUGAGUCCCAGAAGCUGGCACAUUACCAGAGCAAAAAACAUGCCAACAAAGUGAAGAGAUACCUAGCAAUCCAUGGAAUGGAGACAUUAAAGGGGGAAACGAAGAAGCUAGACUCAGAUCAGAAGAGCAGCAGAAGCAAAGACAAGAACCAGUGCUGCCCCAUCUGUAACAUGACCUUUUCCUCCCCUGUCGUGGCCCAGUCGCACUACCUGGGGAAGACCCACGCAAAGAACUUAAAGCUGAAGCAGCAGUCCACUAAGGUGGAAGCUCUGUCAAAACGCCUUACAAAUCCUUUCCUUGUGGCCUCCACCUUAGCCUUGCACCAGAAUAGAGAGAUGAUAGACCCAGACAAGUUCUGCAGCCUCUGCCAUGCAACUUUCAACGACCCUGUCAUGGCUCAACAACAUUAUGUGGGCAAGAAACACAGAAAACAGGAGACCAAGCUCAAACUAAUGGCACGCUAUGGGCGGCUGGCGGACCCUGCUGUCACUGACUUUCCAGCUGGAAAGGGCUACCCCUGCAAAACAUGUAAGAUAGUGCUGAACUCCAUAGAACAGUACCAAGCUCAUGUCAGCGGCUUCAAACACAAGAACCAGUCACCAAAAACAGUGGCAUCAUCCCUGGGCCAGAUUCCAAUGCAAAGGCAACCCAUUCAGAAAGACUCAACCACCUUGGAAGACUAGAGGUGAUUCUGCCCAGCAUCCCAUAUUGGGCCAGCCAUGAGCCAGCUUCCCGUGACUGCUCAGCCCUUGGCUCCCUCUUGCUCGUUGUUCUCACCAGGAAAGUACACGGGCCUGAGGCAGGAUUGGGCCACAGACAGCCUCUCAUUGGUCCGGGCUAAUUCACUCCUGCUGCUCCCCUUUGGCAGGGGUCCUGUAGGUCAUGACAGGGGAGGCAAGGGUAUUGAGAGACUCGGGGUCUCGCGGGGUGGUAGUUUGGAGGGUGGCUUUCCCCAUUUCCCAACCCCUCUGGGCCUUAGGUGCUGAGGCCCCUGCCACCUGUCUUUCCUCUAAAGGUCAGUUUUGGGCCAGUUCUUGCAACUAAAGAGCAGAGAUCUCUCUGGGCCCUAGACAUUUCCAGCAAAACCUGGAACUUUCAUGCCAAACCUGGGGCAGGGCAGGAAACAGAGGAAAUGGCUGCAACAUGGGAGCUUGGAGCUAAUACGACACUCUGCCUUCCCCCAGAAGGUGCAGGCUUUCCUGAGUCUUAGACCAGAUAUGGCCAGUUGCGCAGGUUUCUGCCAACUGUGAAGUAUCCUCCUGGAGCAGUGACACAAUCUUGGCGGAGCAUUGCUACCCCCGCUGCCCCCUCCACAGUUCCUGAAUGGUGCUAAGGAUCUGCAGCAGUUGGCAACGAGCUGGGGCUGGGGGCGGCCUCCAUGUCCACUGAGAUCAUAGGACACUCCAAUGGGGAUGGGACCUUUCCCCUCCUCCAUCAGAGGUGCUCUGACCCUAGGUUACACGGGAAAGUGCCCCACAUGCAAGUCUCCCUGAGGGUUCUGCCCCUAAAGGCAGACUGCCUCAUGCCCGCUAGCUGUGAGGUUCAUUGCUACCCUCGGCCCUACUAGCCCUCUCUUCCCCCUUGUGCAGCGGACCACUUGCCCAGUUUGCUGUGGUGCUAGCCUUCCCCAUCAUCCACCGGGUGAUUUCUGGGUCCCAGGGAAAGAAAGAGAGAGCUGAUGCAGGUUUCUACAGUGAGGAACAGGCGUUUCCCAGGCCCCACACCCAGAUUUCUCUAUCUUUGCUGUGUUUUAUGGCCUGGGACUGAGUCCACACGGAUAGAUUUUUCCUUGUAACCUUGAGACGAGAAUUCCAAGGAGUGUCACCAUCAGAGGCUUCUCUUCAUUGUGUCAAAGAAGCCCCUAGCUGCUCUCGUGGCCUCCUUCCCCCACUCCCUAUCCCUUCACCUGUGAAAUGCCUUUGCUUUGCAUAUUGUGUGUGGAUGUGUGUGUGUGUGUGUGUGUGUUUGUGUGUAUGUGUGUGCUUCUGUGUGUGCCUAAUGCUCUGUCUCUUGGUCACUGAAGCAUCCAAAUAAAGAAUUUCCCUCAUGGGCCAGACUACAACUUAACAGACCUAGGGUUUUGAGCCAUAUUGCCAUUGGAUCUAGUAUGUCUGUCUUGACCCCUCACCCCCACCCCAUUCAGACCUCAGUAGUCCCCAGUAGUCACUUUAGGAGUUGGGACAGAGUCGAGCACCCUGUGAAAGUCUCCCUUGAGUUCAGGUGCCCUGAACUCAGUACAGCCUCAUCUUCUCAUCCACCACCUUCUCCUGCUUCUCCUGUCACAUAGGGCCUCAUGAAGGUCUUUAAAGGGUUUAAGCUGGGGAUCUGCUUUAUGUUUGAGAGAACUGUUCUGGCUGUUAUGUAAAGGAGUGCAGGGAGGGGCAGGAAAGGAGACAAGGAGGCCAGUAUGGACACUGUGUCCAGUAUGGCUUUCCAGGCUAAUCACUUAGGGCAGAGACCCAGCCUUAUUCAUCUCUACUUCCUGAUGUCCAUAGUGGUGUGUCAUGAAUUUUUAUUGAAUGAACAAAUGAGGUGUAUGAGGAGAGAUGGUUUUCUCCUGCUCAGCUCUUACACAGUGAUAGGUUUGUUCCAUGGGACUUAUCAUAGGCCUGGUGAUUCUUGAAAGAGCAUUUUUCAUGACUCAAAAAUGAGCUGAGAAGGAGUGUUAUGGCCAGGUGCGGCGUCAUGCACCUAUAGUCCCAGCUGCUCAGGAGGCUAAGGCAGAAAGACCAUUCAAGCCCAGGAGUUCCAGCCUGAAGUAUGCUGUGAUCAUGCCUGUGAAUAACCACUGCACUCCAGCCAGGGCAACAUAACAAGACUCUAUCUAAAAAAAAAAAAAAAUUAUAAAAAUAAAUUUGAAGGCUGGGCGCCGUGGCUCACGCCUGUAAUCCAAGCACUUUGAGAGGCCAAGGCAGGUGGAUAACCUGAGGUCAGAAGUUCGAGACCAGCCUGGCCAACAUGAUGGCAAAACCCCGUCCCUAUAAAAAAUACGAAAAUCAGCUGCGCCUGGUGGCACACAUCUGUAGUCCCAGCUACUUGGGAGGCUGAGGCAAGAGAAUUGCUUGAACCCGGGAGGCGGAGGGUCGCAUUGAGCCAAGAUCGUGCCACUGCACUCCAGCCUAGGUGACAGAGUGAGACUCCUGUCUCAAAAUAAAUAAAUAAUAAAUUUUAAAAGAAGGUAGCCAGGUGUGGUGGUGCAUUCCUGUAGUCCUGGCUACCUGGAAGGGUGAGGCAGGAGGAUCGCUUUAACCAUGAGUUCAAGGCAGCAGUGAGCUAUGAUUAUGCCACUGUACUCCAGCCUGGACAACAGAGCAAGACCCUGUCUCUAAAAAUAAUAAUUUUUAAAAUUUAAAAAAAGAAAGGAAUGUUAUGGCCUCAAGAGCUCUUUGUCCAUCCUUUACUGUAGACAGCCAGAUUUGAGGAAGGGGCCCAGGCAGCCUCAGCUCCCAUUCAGUGCCACUCAGCCCCUGCUCCUGGUCAGCUGUGAAAGGCUCUACACAGCCCCAAGGGAGGUUCUCAGCUUCCCAUGAUCAGACUGCCUCAGCAAUUCCCCAGAGUCCUUCUAAGCCACCUAGUAUGUCAGAUUCAGCCCCAUCUACCAAGCAAGGAAAUGAAGGGCAGGGGGUGAGUGGGCUAUCAUACCGUGAGCCUCCGGCCUGCAAGACCACUUUGUAGUCCCUACCAGCUGUGUGGCCAGCCCUGUUGGUAAAGGGACCUAGAGAUGAACACUUUCUUGCCCUUAGGGGUUCACACACAGUCAAAGAUCAUGAUGACAAUGAUAAGAAUGCCCAGGAUGCAGGAGCUGACUCAGCCAAGGGCAUGAAAAAGCUGGAGAGGUUGGAAAGCUAGCAUUUCAUCUGCAUAACAACCUUUGAGCUAAGAGUUAAUAUUCCAUAUAGAGAAGGAGGCCAGGCAGGGUGGCUCACAUCUGUAAUCCCAGCACUUUGGGAGGCCAAGGCGGGUGUAUCACUUGCGGCCGGGAGUUUAAGACCAUCCUGGCCAACGUGGUGAAAUCCCAUCUCUACAAAAAAUAAAAAAUAAAAUAAAUAAAAACCAUGGAGAGAAGGAA